CCCCGUAGGCUGUGGGUCAAAAGUGCCGGUCAAAAUGGAAGUGAAUCCCCCUAAACAGGAGCACCUGCUGGCGCUAAAAGGUCCUGUUUCCCUCUGAUUUGGCAAGAGAGACAAUCUUGCAAUAAUAAAUUAACAUUCUAGCUCUGAGGAGUUCAACUAAGAAAUUUUCUCAUCACUAAGAGUAACUGGAUUACUGCAGAAUGACUACAGAAGUAAUAUUACAUUAUCGACCAUGUGAGAGUGAUCCCACACAACUGCCAAAAAUUGCAGAAAAAGCAAUUCAAGACUUUCCUACUCGUCCGCUAUCAAGAUUUAUACCUUGGUUUCCAUAUGAUGGGUCCAAGCUUCCACUCAGACCUAAAAGAUCACCACCUGUGAUUUCUGAAGAGGCAGCUGAAGAUGUGAAACAGUACUUAACCAUUUCAGAACAUGAUGCUAAGUCACACAGUUAUGAUUGCACAGUAGAUCUAUUGGAGUUUCAACCUAGCUUGAAAAAGCAGCAUUUAACCUGGUCACACACACUGAAGGAACAGACUAAUUCUGGAAAUCUGGGUAAACAAUCAGAAAAGGGAAAACAGCACAAGAGGAGAUCUUGGAGUAUUUCCCUUCCCAGCAAUAAUUGUACUAAAAACGUUUCUCCUUUGUCUAAAAAAUUGCAAGAUAGUUUAAAGGCACUAAAUUUACACUCACUUUAUAGAGCAAGAUGGACAAUAGAACACACUAUUUGUAACAGCCAAACUCUGGAAGACAUUUGGACAAAACUCAAUCAAAUUAUUAGGCACAAUGAACUUCCAUCUUGUAAUGCUACAAUUCAGAGGCAUUUAGGCCAAAUAUGGGUGUUCUGUGAUAUUAUGUAUUGUGAAUAUGUGGGAAGUCUUCUUAAAGGAAGAUUAGCUCUUACUGGAAAAAUUAAUUUAUUUGUGCAUAAAUAUGGUGUUAUUUUUAGUAUGUAAUGAAUUCCACUGAUUGUCAAAAAGAAUAUUCUGAAUGAAAUGAAUAUGGAUUGAAAUAGAUAAAAUAAUUUUUACAGGUUUUAAAAUUUUUAAUGACUUUUUAGAAUUCCUAGGCUUGUCAAUUAAGUCAAGAAAUUGCUGAGUUCUGCUUAUUGGCAGCCUUCUUUUAAAUGUGAUAAAUUAUUGUUUACACUGAAUUUGAAGGUAAAAAUGUUCUGUUCCUUUUGUUACAAACUGUGAUUGAAUUAGUCAUGAAUUAAGUUGUAUAGUUUGGAUUUUGGUUAAUCUCUAAAAUCUAAUUUUACUGUAUUUUUUUCCUUACCUCAAGUGUAAUUUUUUAAAAAAUAAAACUCGAAACAAUUCUCUUUGGAGUGCUAUUUAUGUGGCAUGAAUGUAGUUCAAAGUGGGAGACUAGUCUAGAUUUAUAAUGAUGUUUCCAAAGAUAUGUAAUAACAAUUGAUAGGCUGUUUUCAAACAACGAUACAAAAUGUAUACUUUGCCUAAAACGAUAAUGUAUCCUGUUUUGAAGGAAAGUAUCAAAUGUUGAAUGAUUGUUUAUUUCUUCUAAUACAGAUAAUUCAGUAUUAA